CUGGGGCUCCGGGACAUGGUCAGGAGAGGUUGGUCUGUCUGUACCGCCAUUCUCUUGGCCAGACUGUGGUGUCUGGUCCCUACUCACACCUUCCUGUCAGAGUAUCCAGAGGCCGCAGAGUAUCCACACCCUGGCUGGGUGUACUGGCUACAGAUGGCUGUGGCUCCAGGUCACCUGCGUGCCUGGGUGAUGAGAAAUAAUGUCACAACAAAUAUCCCAUCUGCAUUCUCUGGGACACUGACCCAUGAAGAGAAAGCAGUUCUCACAGUUUUUACAGGCACAGCCACAGCCGUGCAUGUACAGGUGGCAGCUUUAGCUUCUGCUAAACUGGAGAGCUCAGUGUUUGUGACAGACUGCGUGUCCUGCAAAAUCGAAAAUGUCUGUGAUUCAGCUCUUCAGGGAAAAAGGGUGCCGAUGUCUGGCCUACAGGGCUCAAGCAUUGUCAUCAUGCCCCCAUCCAACCGUCCACUCAAGGCCAGUGCGGCAUCCUGCACGUGGUCAGUCCAAGUCCAGGGAGGGCCCCAUCACCUGGGGGUGGUCGCUAUCAGUGGCAAAGUCUUGUCAGCAGCUCAUGGGGCAGGAAGGGCCUAUGGUUGGGGGUUUCCUGGCGAUCCCAUGGAGGAAGGAUACAAGACCCUCCUGAAAGGAAUUUCCGGGAAGUUCAAUAGUGGUGAGUUGGUGGCCAUUAUGGGUCCUUCCGGGGCCGGGAAGUCCACGCUGAUGAACAUCCUGGCUGGAUACAGGGAGACGGGCAUGAAGGGGGCCGUCCUCAUCAACGGCCUGCCCCGGGACCUGCGCUGCUUCCGGAAGGUGUCCUGCUACAUCAUGCAGGAUGACAUGCUGCUGCCGCAUCUCACUGUGCAGGAGGCCAUGAUGGUGUCGGCACAUCUGAAGCUUCAGGAGAAGGAUGAAGGCAGAAGGGAAAUGGUCAAGGAGAUACUGACAGCGCUGGGCUUGCUGUCUUGCGCCAACACGCGGACCGGGAGCCUGUCAGGUGGUCAGCGCAAGCGCCUGGCCAUCGCGCUGGAGCUGGUGAACAACCCUCCAGUCAUGUUCUUCGAUGAGCCCACCAGCGGCCUGGACAGCGCCUCCUGCUUCCAGGUGGUCUCGCUGAUGAAAGGGCUCGCUCAAGGGGGUCGCUCCAUCAUUUGCACCAUCCACCAGCCCAGCGCCAAACUCUUCGAGCUGUUCGACCAGCUUUACGUCCUGAGUCAAGGACAAUGUGUGUACCGGGGAAAAGUCUGCAAUCUUGUGCCAUAUUUGAGGGAUUUGGGUCUGAACUGCCCAACCUACCACAACCCAGCAGAUUUUGUCAUGGAGGUUGCAUCCGGCGAGUACGGUGAUCAGAACAGUCGGCUGGUGAGAGCGGUUCGGGAGGGCAUGUGUGACUCAGACCACAAGAGAGACCUCGGGGGUGAUGCCGAGGUGAACCCUUUUCUUUGGCACCGGCCCUCUGAAGAGGUAAAGCAGACAAAACGAUUAAAGGGGUUGAGAAAGGACUCCUCGUCCAUGGAAGGCUGCCACAGCUUCUCUGCCAGCUGCCUCACGCAGUUCUGCAUCCUCUUCAAGAGGACCUUCCUCAGCAUCAUGAGGGACUCGGUCCUGACACACCUGCGCAUCACCUCGCACAUUGGGAUCGGCCUCCUCAUUGGCCUGCUGUACUUGGGGAUCGGGAACGAAGCCAAGAAGGUCUUGAGCAACUCCGGCUUCCUCUUCUUCUCCAUGCUGUUCCUCAUGUUCGCGGCCCUCAUGCCUACUGUUCUGACAUUUCCCCUGGAGAUGGGAGUCUUUCUUCGGGAACACCUGAACUACUGGUACAGCCUGAAGGCCUACUACCUGGCCAAGACCAUGGCAGACGUGCCCUUUCAGAUCAUGUUCCCAGUGGCCUACUGCAGCAUCGUGUACUGGAUGACGUCGCAGCCGUCCGACGCCGUGCGCUUUGUGCUGUUUGCCGCGCUGGGCACCAUGACCUCCCUGGUGGCACAGUCCCUGGGCCUGCUGAUCGGAGCCGCCUCCACGUCCCUGCAGGUGGCCACUUUCGUGGGCCCAGUGACAGCCAUCCCGGUGCUCCUGUUCUCGGGGUUCUUCGUCAGCUUCGACACCAUCCCCACGUACCUACAGUGGAUGUCCUACAUCUCCUAUGUCAGGUAUGGGUUCGAAGGGGUCAUCCUCUCCAUCUAUGGCUUAGACCGGGAAGAUCUGCACUGUGACAUCGACGAGACGUGCCACUUCCAGAAGUCGGAGGCCAUCCUGCGGGAGCUGGACGUGGAAAAUGCCAAGCUGUACCUGGACUUCAUCGUACUCGGGAUUUUCUUCAUCUCCCUCCGCCUCAUUGCCUAUUUUGUCCUCAGGUACAAAAUCCGGGCAGAGAGGUAAAACACCUGAAUGCCAGGAAACAGGAAGAUUAGACACUGUGGCCGAGGGCACGUCUAGAAUCGAGGAGGCAAGCCUGUGCCCGACCGACGACACAGAGACUCUUCUGAUCCAACCCCUAGAACCGCGUUGGGUUUGUGGGUGUCUCGUGCUCAGCCACUCUGCCCAGCUGGGUUGGAUCUUCUCUCCAUUCCCCUUUCUAGCUUUAACUAGGAAGAUGUAGGCAGAUUGGUGGUUUUUUUUUUUUUAACAUACAGAAUUUUAAAUACCACAACUGGGGCAGAAUUUAAAGCUGCAACACAGCUGGUGAUGAGAGGCUUCCUCAGUCCAGUCGCUCCUUAGCACCAGGCACCGUGGGUCCUGGAUGGGGAACUGCAAGCAGCCUCUCAGCUGAUGGCUGCACAGUCAGAUGUCUGGUGGCAGAGAGUCCGAGCAUGGAGCGAUUCCAUUUUAUGACUGUUGUUUUUCACAUUUUCAUCUUUCUAAGGUGUGUCUCUUUUCCAAUGAGAAGUCAUUUUUGCAAGCCAAAAGUCGAUCAAUCGCAUUCAUUUUAAGAAAUUAUACCUUUUUAGUACUUGCUGAAGAAUGAUUCAGGGUAAAUCACAUACUUUGUUUAGAGAGGCGAGGGGUUUAACCGAGUCACCCAGCUGGUCUCAUACAUAGACAGCACUUGUGAAGGAUUGAAUGCAGGUUCCAGGUGGAGGGAAGACGUGGACACCAUCUCCACUGAGCCAUGCAGACAUUUUUAAAAGCUAUACAAAAAAUUGUGAGAAGACAUUGGCCAACUCUUUCAAAGUCUUUCUUUUUCCACGUGCUUCUUAUUUUAAGCGAAAUAUAUUGUUUGUUUCUUCCUAA